AGCCCCGCCCCCAACAUGGCGUCUCACUGACAGUUGGUUGCCGAGCGGCAGAGGCGGAUCCUGCUCCUGAGGGCGGCGGCGGCGGCGGCGGCGGCGGCGGCGGCAGGGCCGGGGUCUCCCGGGCCGGGGUCGGGGGUAUGGCGACUCGGACCGCCUAGGGCGGAGUUGCACGGGCGAGGCAGCAAGUGGGGCGCCGCUGGCGGGCGCGGCGGCCGCUGCCAUGGACUGGUGAUCGCGGCGGCUCCUGCUCCGUUUCCCCCGGCCGGGCGUCUGCUCCUCAGCGCCAAGCCUUCAGCCGGGGCCAUGGGCUCGUCGGCGGCCGCGGCGGCGGCGGCGGCGGCGGCCGCUGACUCGGCGCAGUGGCUCUCGGUGAAGGAAGAGACCAUCUUCCUGCACGACGGGCUGAUCCGGGUCACCGACCUGGCCGAGCUGCCCAGCGAGAUCCUCGGGGCCCCAGAGGCCGCGGACACCGACCUGGAGAUUUUAACCUUUGAGACCAAGAACCCGUCGGAAUUAGCAGAACGUUUGCGCUCUGUUUGUGGGAAUCAGAGCAAUGCCUAUGCCCGGCUGCUGGAAUACCGCCUGAAUGCCUUGCGAGGACUGUGGAAUGCCCAGCGCCAGCUGGCCUUAGAAGAACAGCAUGAAAGGGAAAGUUCAGGUGAUGAGGAAACUUUGGCCCUGCUCAAACGCCAGGGCUUGUUGCAGCAACCUGAGCAAGCGCCCUUCACAUCGAGGAUGGGGCUCCUGCUGGUCUUCCCCCUUAUUCAGUCCCAGAGUAGAACAGACCCCUCUCUCUGUAACAUAACUGCUGAGGUGCUAUUGAACUGCCUUCGUGACUGCCAGCCUUUGAGCUUGACCAAGGAGCCUGCUGACUGUCUCAAUGGAAUUGAAACUUUGCUGUGCUCUUGGCUAGAGGAGACUUCUGACACAGGCCGACACAUCCCACAUAAGCAAAAAGAAAAUGCUGCUGCUGCCCUGGUGGCUUUGGCUUGUGCCAGGGGAUCAUUGAAAACUUUCGUCCACACAGUCCAUCUAUUACAGAAACAGACGGAUCUAGGGUCCCUGCCUGUAGCUGAUGUGCUAUAUAGGCUGUUGCUUUUGGAAGGGGGGCCUGGAUCUCCCUCCUGUUUGCUUGGGGGCAAACACAUAGUAUCAUGGGGUUAUGAAGACAUGUUGCCUGCGCCGGAUAGCAACACUGGCUCCAGUUCUGAAAAUAAAGAUGCUGACUUGGGACGCUGUCUCACGGCAGAUGGUCUUUACCUGUAUACUACUAACUCAGUUGGAAGAGGAGUAAGCAAAUUGGGAUCUGGAUUACAUGGUACUCUCAGAGGUUUUGUGUACUGCCGGAACGAGGAGUUGGAACCAGGAUGGGUGGCUUUUGGCAGCGGCAGUCUUCUCCACCGGCCUGUCUCUUUCGAUAAUAAACCUCACUCCCUUUUCCAGGUCAUUGACCAGAACACCCUUCAGGUGUGCCAGGUGGUGCCAAUGCCAGCCAAUCACCUCCCCAUUGGCAGCACCAUGAGCACUGUGCACCUGUCUUCAGAUGGCACUUACUUCUAUUGGAUCUGGUCUCCUGCCAGCCUGAAUGAGAAAACACCGAAGGGACAUUCUGUCUUCAUGGACAUUUUUGAACUUGUGGUUGAAAAUGGUGUAUUUGUAGCCAACCCACUUCAGGAACGUACAAUUCUAAUGAGAAAAGAGGGCGAAUCUGCCAAAAGCAUUAAUGAGAUGCUUCUAAGUAGACUUUCUCGGUAUAGAGCCUCCCCGUCAGCAACGCUUGCUGCCCUGACUGGUUCCACCAUCUCCAACACACUGAAAGAGGAUCAAGCAGCAAAUACUAGCUGUGGGCUGCCUCUAAAAAUGCUGCGGAAGACACCCAUAUAUACCUGUGGCACCUACUUGGUGAUGCUGGUGCCUCCUCCAGGGGGAUCAGGCAGCUCUGCCACCCGAUCUCUUUUUGGUGGAACAAGUGGUUUGUCAUCUUUAAAAAUCCUAGCCUCCAGCUUGGUGUAUAAUAUUUCGGAUGGUCAGUUUACAAGUCGUGCAGAUCUCAUAGAUGCUGCUGGAAGCUCACUGGGGCGUGGUGCUCUCGUACCAGGAUUGGGAGCGUGUUAUGACACAGUGAACAACAUGCUAUGGACAUGCUCAAAUGACUAUAUCGAUCAGUGGUGUAACCCUGGGAAUCAAGCCUUCCAUUAUGUCUGCCAGAGACUUGGAGUCAGUCACAUUAUCACUGAGCCCAAAGAAGAGGCUAUAACCACGAAUGAGGUUAUAAACCAAUUAUUGCACCACGUUGGUGCGAUGUGCAUACACCAACUCAAUCUUCUUGCCACCAACCCCAAUCUUCCAAUCACAAGUGUCUUGGGCAAGCAGCAUCCAAUUGAAGCACAUCAUCUUAGCAGUAUUUGUGACAUUAUGGAGAAGGCCAUGGUUAAUGGAGAUACCUGUAUUAUACGCUGCAUUCUCGUUGUCUUUCAGGUGGUAUUUAAAUUUUUCUUCAGCCCACAAACUGAAAGGAAUCGAGACAUCAUUCGACGGUCGGGAUUGCUUCUUUGGCAGUUGUUGAUGGCUCCAAAAGAUCAAAUUUGCCCUGAAAUUCAGAAGGAAGUCUGCCUUGCCAUCAGCUCUGGUUUAAAUAUCUUGUACCCAGGUGAAACUGAAAUCAAUAACUUACUUAAACUGGUCUUAACAGAAGGAGAGAGAAACAGUGGACUCUCCCAGCUACGGGAUGUGAUCCUAACCAACCUGGCUGAACAGCUCCAAAACAACCGAUUUGGCAGUGAUGAGGAUGAUCAUUACAGACUAAAUGAUGAACUUUUACACUACAUUCUGAAGAUUGUUGUACGAGAAUCCUGUAUCUUAAUCACCAAGUGCCAAACUGUCUCUAAAGAUGAUUUUCAAAAGCUCCUUUCAACUGUGCCUGCUGCAUCCUCCUGCCUGCGCUAUCUGAUGGCAGUUCAGAAUCACCUUCUCAGUAACACUAUUUUGAUUAAACCUGAUGAGAAUGAUGACAGUGACAGCUCCUUGCAGGGAGAGACAUUGAAGGUACAGGAGCUAAAAGUCAGUAUUUUGGCUCUUGCCACCCAAAUCCUGACUGGAUGUGAUGAAGUGUUGGAAAUGCUACAGCAGGUCACAACUGCCCUCAUAAAUAGUGACAUAGCAGACCGUGAGCAGAGGUUAAAAGGCUUGGAACAAGUUACUAAGGCUACUAUGCUUGGUCACCUUCUUCCAGUGUUACUGACCUCCUUGAUGCAUCCAAAUUUACAGACUCUGAUCAUGGCGGAUGCCCUGAUGCCUCAGCUAGUGCAGCUGGUACUCUAUACCAGCCAGACGGCGUUGCUGCUUAAAACCCAGUGUCCGGUUUUUGCUGAGGUGGGCUGUUCCCCGUGUGGUGCACCAGACCAGAAGUGCAGGCUGUUCCCUGAUGAGAGAAUGUUAGAAGAGAAGGAAGAGCCAGGAUUUCUCACUGGUUUAAAGAUUCCUGCCCCAUGGGCUGCUGGAAAGACUGUGGAAACAGUCCACCCCGUCAGAGACAACUAUAAAUUUAAAGAAACGGUCCAUAUCCCAGGAGCUCGCUGCCUGUACCUUAGAUUUGAUAGCAGAUGCUCUUCGCAAUAUGACUAUGACAAAUUGGUGAUAUAUGCGGGGCCUAACACAAACAGUAGGAAGGUUGCUGAAUAUGGAGGCAACACACUGGGAUAUGGCAGCCGUAGUGUCUUAGGAACUGGUUGGCCGAAAGACUUGGUGAAGUGCAUUUCCCCCCCUUCCUUAAAUUUUAAGGUGGAAGGAGAUACAGUCACCUUCUCCUUUGAAAUGAGAAGUGGCCGUGAACACAACACUCCUGAUAAAGCCAUGUGGGGCUUUGCUUGCACAGUUCGCGCUCAGGAGUCUUCGGAGGAUGUCUCAGGAGGCUUGCCCUUUCUGGUAGACCUGGCUUUAGGUCUGUCUGUGUUAGCUUGUUCCAUGUUAAGAAUCCUGUACAAUGGACCAGAAAUUACCAAAGAAGAAGAAGCCUGUCAGGAGCUAUUGCGGUCCAAACUUUUACAAAGGUGCCAGUGGCAGGUGGAGGCCAAUGGCGUGAUCUCCCCUGCCCUUACUCCGAGCCCCUCUCCACUGCCUCUGACCAUAGAGGAAGACAGAGAAUUCACCUACCCCUCUGAUGUCCUCGUGCCUCCUGUUGGAAACUACUUUGAUCUGCCUCGGAUCAGACUGCCUCCAGGAAUCAUGAUAAAGCUCAGGGAAAUUUCUGGGCGUGCUAGACCUCAAUUUAGACCAAGUAUAAAAGAAGUGAUUCAGCCAGACGUGAUGGAGGAAAUGGUGGUAUCUUGUGUUAUUAAGCACUUGAACUUGGUUGAUGCACUGCAGUCUCUAAUAAAUUUCCAAUAUCAAGAAGAACAUGCUGAAGAAUAUGAUUUAUUAUGUAAAAUUAUGGGAGAGACCUUUAAGAAACUCAAUGCCAUGGAGAGACAGCUGCAGAGUGUUGCAGAACUGGAACAAAAAUGGCAAAGUGAAGUUGAUGAUGCCAUGCAGGGGAAACUGGAGAACAACAUGCCUUUCUUUUAUGAUUACCAUUUUAAUGAGAACAAAAUGAAAGAACUAGAACUUUUAUGUUCAAUGAAGGAAGUCUCCUUUGAUGGGAAUGAUCUUGAAAACAUGGUCCUAUCACUGAGGGAGAAGUUCCUACAAGAAGUGAAUUCUCUUAUUCAGAAACCCUCACACCCACUGGCUAAAACAAAGACGUUAGUGAAGAGUUUAAUGAACCGAGCCGAGCUGUUGCUGCAUGUCACCAUCGCAGCCCAGUCGGGCCUCACGAGAAGCAUCUCUGGGACCCCUGCUGAAACACCAGCUUGUAAAUCAGCUUCUGAAACAAAAGUGAUAUCUCACGCUGUCAGGCAGCCUGUUUUUCUUCGCAGCAUGUCAGCUCCUUCUGACCUGGAAAUGAUUGGUAAUGAAGAUUUGGAAUUUACUAGAGCAAAUCAGAGGCGUCGCCACGUGACCAGCCACCGCAGCAGCUCCUUUACACUCCUGCAGUCGCUGGCCAUUGAGGACAGCAGGGACAAGCCCACCUACAGUGUCCUGCUAGGGCAGCUGUUUGCUUUCAUCGGCACCAACCCUGACCAAGCUGUGUCCAGCAGCAGUUUCCUUUUGGCUGCACAGACAAGGUGGCGGCGGGGAAACACUCGCAAGCAGGCACUGGUGCACAUGCGGGAAUUGCUGACAGCUGCCGUACGAGUCGGGGGAGUGACGCAUCUUGUGGGUCCAGUGACGAUGGUCCUUCAGGGAGGACCCAGAAUUGAAGAACUCACAUGUGGUGGGAUGGUCGAGCAGGUCCAGGAAGCCUUUGGCGAGACCAUGACCUCUGUUGUGUCUCUGUGUGCUCGUUACCCUAUCGCUUGCGCAAAUAGCAUUGGACUCUUAUGUACCAUACCUUACACCAGGAGCGAAGAGAAGUGCCUGGUACGCAGUGGCCUUGUGCAGCUCAUGGAUCGACUGUGUAGCUUGAGCAAUCAGACCGAGUCCAGCUCCAGUGAGAAACAGACCAAGAAGCAGAAGGUGGCCACCAUGGCCUGGGCUGCCUUCCAGGUGCUUGCCAACCGCUGUGUUGAGUGGGAAAAAGAGGAAGGUGGCUCCACAGAGGCUGUGCACUCAGGUCUGGCCCGGCAGGUGUCCAGCCUUCUCACUAACCAUCUUGCCCGAGCCACAGAGUGCUGUGGCAACCAGGCUGCUGGGAAUGACGCGCUCCAGGAUGUCCUUAGUCUUCUCAAUGAUCUCUCAAGGAGCCACAUAGGUAAAGCCAUCCUGAGCCAGCCAGCUUGUGUGUCCAAACUCCUCUCCCUGCUGCUUGACCAACGCCCGUCUCCAAAGCUAGUCCUUAUUAUUCUCCAGCUGUGCCGGGCGGCGCUGCCCCUGAUGAGCGUAGAAGACUGUGGAAACGUGGAGCUCCCACCCUGGAGCUACUCUGUCCCCUCCUUAAACAGUGAGCAGGAGGAUCCCAGCGACCCAGCUUCCAAGAUCGCCUCCCUGCUCUUAGCAAAGCUGGCAGAUUAUGUGGUUCCAGGAUGUCAGACAGUUCUUUCUCCAACCGCUUCUGAACCUGACACCACAUUGACAAAAACCAGUCCCAAGAAUUCCUUGAAAGGAGAUAAAGAUCCUGGAGAAGAGAGUGAGGCUGUGGAUGGCAAGCUCUCGAUAUUUAUCCACAAGCGGGAAGACCAGUCAUCCCAUGAAGUCCUCCAGCCAUUGCUAAGUAGUUCAGAAGGACGGCCCUUCCGACUUGGUACUGGCGCCAACAUGGAGAAAGUUGUGAAGAUGGAUCGAGACAUGACCAAGGGUGGCUGUUGCGAAGUGAUUACAGAAGAGGCUGCAGCCGCCCUGCGGAAAGCCACCAAGUGGGCACAGUCAGGCCUCAUCGUCAGCAUUGGGCCACCUGUAGAGUCUAUCAACCCAGAGACUGUGAGUGGACUAUCCACAGGCGACAAAAAGAAAACUGCCCAAACUUCCAUUUGCCGAGAGAGGAACUCGGAGCUUGCAAGGACUGAUCCUGUGCGUCCCUUCAUCAGUGGGCAUGUGGCAAACAGCAUGGCUGCAGAAGUGAUCGCCUUGCUACAUAGCUUGCUCAUGGCACCUGAAUCAAAUGCUGCUCAAAUAUGGACCACAACAGCAGAGAAGGUUCUGUCUAGAGCACUGAUGUACAUUCCACAAUUGGGGAAAUACGCAGAAAGCAUUCUGGAAAAUGGCAGCAGCAGUGGCAGGAAACUUGCCAAACUUCAGAGAAUUGCACGCCAGGCCGUUGCCGCACUGUGUGCACUUGGAGGCUUCAAAGAGACAAUCAAGAUAGGAUCCGAGGUUCAGGUUUUAGGUAGAGGAAUUUCAGGAAGCAUUGGAGUAGUGGCUUCUAUCAAUGAACAGGAAGGUAUAGCUACAGUCAGAUUCCCACCCAUAGACUGUAGAAAGACUUCGCAAGCGUCAGACACAUUGACUAUUCCAUUGUCUAGACUUUGUGUUCCAAGAUCAGAGGCAUUGCCUCUUCAUAAACUGUCCAUUACUGAGAAGGUAGUACAGGCAGUCCAGUCCAUGUUGCUUCCUCAGGAGGGAAGUCUCUCUAUUCACACCUCACUUCCUGCAACAGGAGAUGGGUCAGCUCCUGUGAUGGCAGUCGUUCGGCUCCUUGCUGAAAUAAGGACAAGAGCAUGCCUGGUCAUGGCCCAGCUUUUAGAAGACAGCUUAUUUUGUGAAGAAUUCAUACAACAAUGUCCAGCAGCUGUUGAAGUUCUUAACCUAGUAGCCCAGGAAUGUAGUGCUGGAGAGCGACUUGCAGUUGUGGAGGUACAGUGUGAACGGCUGAGGAUGCUCUACCGGGACUGUGCUCGGCCCCCACCACCUCCUUUGCAGGCUGACCGAAGACAGCCCAAAGAGAUUACUUGGAGCCCCUCGCGAGUGUUUCCGCCUGUUCGAGCCUGCAUGUUCUCAUCUCACCUUACCUCAGUCACCUUCCUGGCUGACCCCAGCGCUGGGGGAGGCCUGCCCCGGGGCACUUUUAUCUAUGCCACUUCACCACUGCCAGUUCAGGCCCCGUCUUUUUACUGGGAAAUUGAAAUCGUUUCCUAUGGAGACACCGAUGAUGACACCGGACCCAUAGUUUCCUUUGGCUUCACUACAGAAGCAGAGAAGCGAGAUGGGGCUUGGACUAAUCCAGUGGGCACUUGUCUUUUCCAUAACAACGGCCGAGCCGUGCACUAUAAUGGCUCCAGUUUGUUACAGUGGAAGAGCGUUCGCUUAGACGUGACUCUCUCCCCCGGUGACGUGGCAGGAAUUGGCUGGGAGAGAACUGAGGGGACUCCACCUCCUCCGGGACAGCCAGCCAAGGGCCGGGUGUACUUCACAUACUGCGGGCAGCGCCUCUCACCAUAUCUUGAAGACGUCUCUGGUGGCAUGUGGCCAGUGGUUCACAUUCAGAAAAAGAACACCAAAACCCGAGCUAACUUUGGCUCCCGGCCGUUUGCCUACGCGGAAGGGCAGGCCCACCGCAAUGCUGCUGACCUGUGCACUGACCUAGCAGAAGAGAUCAGCGCUAACUUUGAGGCCCUGCCUUUCGCCAUGGCAUCUGACAGUGACAAUGAUGCUGGCACCAGUAUUGCAUCAGACCCAGGCACUCAUGGGCCACCAUGCCGGAUUGCUGCCGUGGCCACCGCUCAGCAACAAUAUGAUAGUGACACCUCCUGUCAUUAUAAAGUCGAGCUCAGCUAUGAGAAUUUCAUCACCUCUGGCCCAGACCCUCACCCGCCUCCCAUUGCAGAUGAUGAAAGCGAUGAUGAUGACGAUGAUGACAUCCCUCAGGAGGACCACUACGCCCUGCUGGUGAAAGCAUGGGAGACCAAGGUUUUUCCUACCAUCCGAAGACGCUUCCGCAAUGAAGCAGAGCGGAAAUCGGGCCUGGACCAGAUAAAGGGGGCCUUACAACUAGGUAUGGUGGAUAUUGCCCGACAGACGGUUGAAUUUCUCUACGAAGAGAAUGGUGGCAUCCCAAGAGACCUUUAUCUUCCCACCAUUGAAGACAUUAAAGACGAAGCAAACAAGUUCACAAUUGAUAAAGUUCGAAAAGGUCUCACAGUAGUAACCCGCUCUCCAGACAGCAAUAAUGUAGCCAGCAGUGCUGUUGGAACUGCUCUGCCAAAAUUUGCCAUCCGAGGGAUGCUGAAAACCUUUGGGCUUCAUGGAGUCGUCUUAGAUGUUGAUUCAGUGAAUGAACUGGUGCAGGUAGAAACGUACCUCCGCAGUGAAGGUGUGCUGGUGCGAUACUGGUAUCCUAUUGACAUGUUGGAAAGGCCCCCAGCAGGCUACCGAAGGACUGCCACCAAUGGGCUGGUCACACUGGACAAUACCAACCUUCAAAUUCACAGGGAGCUGCUGCGCUGCGAGGCUGCGCUGGCCAGGCUGUACUGCCGCAUGGCCCUGCUCAAUAUCUUCGCCCCGAAGUUGCCUCACUUGUUCACUCGCCUCUUCCACAUCCCUGCCAUCCGGGACAUUACCCUGGAGCACCUGCAACUGCUGUCCAAUCAGCUCCUCGCACCUCCUCUCCCAGACGGCACCAUCAGCUCCAGCUCGAUCCUCCUGGCGCAGUCUUUACAGCAUUGCAUCCAUUCCCAGAACUGCUCCGCCACGGACCUCUUUUACCAGGGCAACUCCCAGACAGUGAGAGAGUGGCUCAACGUGGCCAUCACCCGGACCCUGCACCAGGGCGAGGAGAGCCUUUUAGAGCUGACGAAACAGAUCUGCUCUUUCCUGCAGACAGCACCAGAGCAGUUCCCCUCCGAAGAGUUCCCAAUUUCCGAAUCCAAAGUCAACAUGGACGUGAAUUUCCCCGGGGCAGCUUUUGUUGUUGUGUCUUGUAAAGAAAGUCAAUCUGGAUUCCGCAAAGACUCCUCUCUGUACAAGGCACCGUGGGCACGGGUGCUCGUAUAUGGCCUCGGCCACAAAGUGAAGCGAAAUGGCCAGCUGAACCUCAUCGAGGCCGCCUGUUACCCGCGGGACGCGUCCCCAGCCAACACUGGGCUUGCACCUCCCCCCACCGCUGACCAGUACCCCUCUGUGGUCCUCUCCACAGACAGGGUCCACAUCAAACUGGGGGUGUCUCCACCUCCUGGAGCAGUCCUGGUGUUACAUUCCCUGCCCCUGGAGUUCCCACUGGCUAUGGCCUUCGCAGAGCAGCUGCUGUCCUGGAAAUCAGAGGACAGUGAAGGGAAGUCCGAAGAUGAGCCUGACACCAUUCCGACAUCCGUCCUCCUGCAGGUGGUGGAGCUGCUAGGAAACUUCUUGUGGACCACGGACAUGGCAGCCUGCGUGAAGGAGCUUGUUUUCCAUCUCCUGGCAGAGCUCCUGCGCACGGUGCACACCCUGGAGCAGAGGCGGCACCCCGCUGGCCUGUCCUCCUCAAUCGCCCUCCAGCUGAACCCCUGCCUGGCCAUGCUGAUGGCCUUGCAGUCGGAGCUCCACAAGCUGUACGACGAGGAGACGCAGAACUGGGUCUCAGGCGGCGCCUGCGGGGGCUCCGGGGGGGCGGCGGCCGGUGACCAGGGCAGGUUCUCUACGUAUUUUCAUGCACUCAUGGAAGGGUGCCUGGCUGUGGCCGAAGUGACCCUGCCUACUAACAUGAGUGUCACAGCCAGUGGGGUGACCUCAGCGACCGCCCCAAAUCUCAGUGACUCGUCCUCCUCCUCCUCGUCCUCCCCAGGACAGACCCCACAGAGUCCCAGCCUCCUCUCCAAGAGGAAAAAAGUCAAGAUGAAGCGGGAAAAGGCCUCCUCGUCGGGCAAGCGCCAGUCUUCCCGCACCGUGGACUCGGACCCCACCGUGCUCAGCAUCGGAGGCAGCAAGCCCGAGGACAUGCUGUGGUUCCACCGCGCACUCACCCUGCUCAUCAUCCUCCGCCACCUCACCAGGAAGGACCCACAGGGGCUGGGCGUGACGAGUGACGCCAUCGCCGAUGCCUGCCAGGCCCUGGUGGGCCCCACCGCCCACAGCCGCUUGCUGGUGAUCUCCGGGAUCCCCACCCACCUGGACGAGGGCGUAGUCAGAGGCGCCAUCCGCAAGGCCUGCAACGCCCACGGCGGGGUCUUCAAAGACGAGAUCUACAUCCCGCUGCAGGAAGAAGACACCAAGAAGCCAAAAGACAAGGCCGAGGGCGGGGACGGGAAAGUUGAGCCCGAGAAGACACUGGCCUUCCCCGGCACAGACAGCAUGGAGGUCAGCACGUCCAGCAGCCUGACCCCCGCCAUGAGCAUCAGCGCCUCCGCCUCCACCAGCCAGGCCUCCAUCUGCAGCUCGCAGGGCAUCUCCCAAACCGUCAGCGACCUCUCUGUGGAUCCGCUGCCUGCCGGCCUCGAGCUGCCCAUCCCUCCGGGCCUGUUGGAGCCCCACGCGGUGUCCAGCCAGGAAAGCCUGGACAUUUCCCUGUGCAGCACCGGCAGCCUGGGCAGCCUGGGCAGCCUGGGGGAGCCCCUGGACAAUGCAGAGACGGCCUCGGUGUCGGACAUGGGCUCCAUGUACACAGUCACUUCCCUGGACAACCAGCCCCUCGCCGCCCGCCCCAUCAAAGGCUUCGCAGUCGUGGAGAUAAGAUCCCGAGCCAAAAUUGAGAAAAUUCGAGCAAGUUUAUUUAACAAUAAUGACUUGAUUGGUUUGUCAAGUUUGGAUGGUGAAGAUGAAUUGAUGGAAAUGUCAACAGAAGAGAUUCUAACCGUGUCUGUAGUAAAUCAGAGUCUCUUUGAUACUCAAGGGAGCCCAGGGUUAGAAGAUUAUUUCAAUGAUAAGUCAAUUAAAGGGGAGAAGCUGGUGCCCGGAGCCAGAGAGGUUCUGACGGAGAUAUUUAAGAGUUGUGCCCAUUCAGAGCAGACGCUGAGCCUGACACCAGCGAAGCCCAUCAGAGUCUCUGACAUUUAUCUUAGCAAAGAGCAGAUCAACUCCCAGACCCCAGGCAACCUCCUCCACCUCUUCUUCACCAAUGUCCGGCCGCCAAAAAAGGUGCUGGAGGAUCAGCUCACCCAGAUCCUGAGGAAGUAUGGCGUGCCAAAGCCCAAGUUUGACAAGAGCAAGUACAGCAAGGCCGGGAAGGAGCAGCACCCCGUGAAGGUGGUGAGCACCAAGCGGCCUAUCACCAAGCCGCCCGCCAAGGACAAGGCUGUGCUCAACAGCGUCAGCAGGACUGCCUUAAGUGAGAAGAAGCCAACUGUGAAGCCAAAAUCACCAGAAAAGAGCAAACCAGAUGAAAAGGACCCAGAAAAGUCACCUACCAAAAAACAAGAAGUCCCUGAGGAAAAAUACCUGACGCUGGAAGGAUUUCACAAAUUUGUUAUUGACCGAGCCAGGCAAGAUAUCCGUAGCGUCUGGAGGGCGAUCUUGUCCUGUGGUUACGAUCUUCACUUUGAGAGGUGCGCAUGCAUCGAUGUCCGACAUGCACAGAAGGCCUCAAGAAAGUGGACCCUGGAGAUGGACGUGGCACUUGUGCAGUACAUCAACCAGCUAUGCCGCCACCUCGCCAUCACACCCGCACGGCUCCAUCCCCAUGAGGUGUACCUGGACCCCGCGGAUGCUGCUGACCCCAGAGUGGCCUGUCUCCUGAACGUGCCCAUCGAGAGCCUGCGCCUGCGCUUCGCCUUGCUGCAGUCCCUCAACACCACACUGGAGACCUUCUUCCUGCCCCUGGUGGAGCUGCGCCAGACACCCAUGUAUACCCACAGCAUCGCCGCCCUGCUGAAGGAGGCCAAAGGGCUGAUCUUCUAUGACACGAAGGUGACCGUGAUGAAUCGAGUGCUGAAUGCCACUGUGCAGAGGACAGCGGACCACGCGGCCCCUGAGAUCACCUUGGACCCACUGGAAAUUGUGGGAGGGGAAAUCAGAGCUUCUGAAAACUCCUACUUCUGUCAGGCUGCCAGGCAGCUGGCCUCAGUGCCGUCGUCUCAGCUCUGCGUCAAGCUGGCCAGUGGCGGUGACCCCACAUAUGCCUUCAACAUCCGCUUCACUGGCGAGGAGGUCCAUGGCACCAGCGGCUCUUUCCGCCACUUCCUGUGGCAGGUGUGUAAGGAGCUGCAGAGUUCCUCGCUGUCGCUGCUGCUGCUGUGCCCCAGCUCAGCUGUCAAUAAGAACAAGGGCAAGUAUAUCCUGACCCCGAGCCCCAUCACCUACGGGGAGGAGCAGCUGCUGCACUUCCUGGGGCAGCUGCUGGGGAUUGCAAUUCGGGCAGACGUCCCGCUGCCCCUGGACCUCCUGCCCUCCUUCUGGAAGACGCUGGUGGGCGAGCCCUUGGACCCUGAGCAAGACCUGCAGGAAGCGGAUAUCCUCACCUACAAUUACGUCAAGAAGUUUGAGAGCAUCAAUGAUGAGACCGAGCUGGAGGCCCUGUGCGCUGAGAUCGCCUCCCAGCACCUGGCCACGGAGAGCCCUGACAGCCCCAACAAGCCCUGCUGCAGGUUCACCUACCUGACCAUGACGGGCGAGGAGGUGGAGCUGUGCAGCCGGGGCCGGCACAUCCUUGUGGCGUGGGAGAACAAGGACAUCUACGCGGCAGCCAUCCGGAGCCUGCGGCUGCGGGAGCUGCAGAAUGUGGAGUGCGUGACGGCCGUGCGGGCCGGCCUGGGCUCCAUCAUCCCCCUGCAGCUGCUGACCAUGCUCAGCCCACUGGAGAUGGAGCUGCGCACCUGCGGCCUCCCCUACAUCAACCUCGAGUUCCUCAAGGCCCACACCAUGUACCAAGUGGGGCUGAUGGAGACGGACCAGCACAUCGAGUUCUUCUGGGGGGCCCUGGAGAUGUUCACCCAGGAGGAGCUGUGCAAGUUCAUCAAGUUUGCCUGCAACCAGGAGCGCAUCCCGUUCACCUGCCCCUGCAAAGAUGGGGGUCCCGACACUGCCCAUGUGCCCCCGUACCCCAUGAAGAUCGCCCCCCCAGAUGGCACAGCAGGUUCCCCAGACUCUCGCUACAUCCGCGUGGAGACCUGCAUGUUCAUGAUCAAGCUUCCCCAGUACUCCUCUCUGGAAAUCAUGCUGGAGAAACUUCGUUGUGCCAUUCACUACCGUGAAGACCCCCUCAGUGGCUGAUGGGAGGGAGCCCCAGAAUUAGGCUGUCACUGAGGCACCCACUCUGCUGGCUUGGGAAGCCACCACUGCGGCCCGUCCCUCCAGGGCCCUGCGUGAGGAGUUGGCAACAUUUUGCUUUUCCAAACUUUCGUCCACAUUCCAGGGCCUCCUGGAAGACUUAACCUUUUGUCUUUGUACGUUUCGUGAUGGGUUGGUUCUUUUGCUGCCUGUUUGUGGUCUAUUUGUAGGAUAGUUUAGUUCCCAGACAGUUUGUGUCUAAUUUGAUCUUCUUGGACAUUGUCCCUCAUGGCCACCAGAUUCUAAUGCCAUAAGGCCCCAGCUGGUUCCCCAUCACAGAACCACCCAGCAGGAAGCCGGGGGUACAAUGACCUCGGCCACACAGAGCGCUCGUGCUUUCAGCAGAGCGCCUCCACAGACAAGCCUGUGGCCAGCCCUGCCCUCCAGCCUCGAGCUGGAGUUGCUCCAGAGGCAGCCCCAGCAGGCCUCCCUCCACAUAGAGGUGGCUGGGCCAAUUGCCCAAACACGUGAGACACACAGGGAGCUUUAUGUGUUCAUCUUCCUGCUUUAGAACUUGCUCCCGGUCUUGGUUUUUCUGAGGAAAAGCCCACAGUGGUUCCCCUGCCCCUCCCAUACCUCCCUAUCUGCCGUCUGUCUCUUUGGGCCCUGGUCUGACAGUUUUCAUCUGAGGCCUCCUCGGGAGCAGGAGACUUAAGGGUUCAUCCCGACCUUAGUUCACAGAGCCUAGCUGGGUGCAUCCCAGCCGCAGGGGGUGAGAAGACACCCAGAGAUGGGGGACAAUGCUCAGGUGGGGGCCUCCUCCGAGACUCUGGUUGAGAGGAAAGCACAUGAUUCAAGCCUACCCCACAAAAAAGGAGCACAAAAUGCUCAGAAAUGGCCCUUCCUCCCUGCAGUGACGUAGGACAAGGGAAAGGGCCACACCCAUUUUCAAAAGAGUGGACUGAGGUGCUCUGCUCAAUUUGGGGUCUGCUUUAGUGACCCAGACACUCAAGUCCAGAUGGAGACUCCAGGGGGGUCCUUCUGCCCCUCUGGCCAGCCCCACCCAGCACUCCCCAUCACCCCAUGUAAGUGUGUAUGCCAGGGCUGAGCUGCCUCCAGGCUCACCCACUGCAUCUUUGCCCCAAAUAGGUCUUUGUCCAGUGGUACUUUGUUCAUGAGCAGCACAGGCCAUCUUGUUGGACACUGUCACUUUGGGCCUUGCCAGGUCUCACAGAAUCACAUCGCUGUAUUUAUUGUAUAAUAUUGUGAAUAUUGGAAGUUUUGAGUGAGUGCUGUCUAGAAGGUUUUGGAGUGUGGAUGCUGGUCCAAGAAAGAAGAUGUGCCCUGGCCUGCUGGAAAGAUUGUGAAUUCUAGAGAUAGAGCCGUUAGCAUCCAUCUCCUCCCUGUAACUCUUAGGAAAUGCAUCAAGGACCAUUAUAGAAAGGAUCCCCUGACCUAAGGAUGAAAUCGACCUAGGGUUAAUCAUGACAGCUGCAUCAGUUGUAUUGGAUGCAAGUCAACUCUGGAGGUGAGUGCCCGCAAGCAGUUCCCCUGCUUUGAAAGAAGAUGGUCAGCCCGCUGCCUCCCCAGCGGCCACAGCUCCUUUGAGUGUGGGGGGUCACAGCCAGGAUGUAUUCCUGACAAUAAGGAUCCUUUUAUUUUCAUUUCUGCAUAAUGAAAGAGCCUUUCGAUUUAUUAGAAGUGGUUUUUCCUCCCUACAUCUUUAAAUUCUUGGUUCUCUUUAGUCCUCAUCCCUUGAAUGGACUUGUCAGCUACCUCCCCAGGAGGAGUUCAGAAGCUUCUGUUGGCCAUCACUUGAGUAGAUGACAAGCUGUAAGGUAUCUGCUGCUAACGUGGCUGCUUCUCCGAGAGCACAUUGAGGUCCAGACAGAUCCAAACCUUGGCCCUAAAAAAUGUGUGCUGUAAAGUUACUUGAUGUAUAUUUAUUAUAAUUAUUUAUGGUUGCAUUUAACAAACUUUUCAUUCAAUCUGAUGCUAUUUACACCAUGCUGUGUAAAGGAAGCUCACUAAAGGAAAAAAGUCACACCAAUAAAUAACCUUCAUCUAAUUUUGAUUUACCUUAAGAGUUGUGUGAUCAUCUACUCUUGCUGAGCAAGUUCAAAGGCUGGCAUGCUUGGAUGGCUCUGAUAUUUAAGUGCUGCCAAGUGGCUAGGAAUUAAAGUGUUUCUAAUUAU